GCCAUUCGCUCUUCAGACGCCGGAGACGUAGGAGUGGGUCUUCAGACUCCAAAGGGGUUGGACUAAUGGCGGAUGCUGAGGCGAGGGCUGAGUUCCCGGAGGAGGCCAGACCUGACAGGGGCACCUUGCAGGUGUUGCAAGAUAUGGCCAGCCGCUUGCGAAUCCAUUCCAUCAGGGCCACAUGCUCCACGAGCUCCGGCCACCCUACAUCAUGUAGCAGUUCUUCUGAGAUCAUGUCUGUGCUGUUCUUCUACAUCAUGAGGUACAAGCAGUCAGAUCCAGAGAAUCCGGACAACGACCGAUUUGUCCUCGCAAAGAGACUGUCGUUUGUGGAUGUGGCAACAGGAUGGCUCGGACAAGGACUGGGAGUUGCAUGUGGAAUGGCAUAUACUGGCAAGUACUUCGACAGGGCCAGCUACCGGGUGUUCUGCCUCAUGAGUGAUGGCGAGUCCUCAGAAGGCUCUGUCUGGGAGGCAAUGGCCUUUGCUUCCUACUACAGUCUGGACAAUCUUGUGGCAAUCUUUGAUGUGAACCGCCUGGGACACAGUGGUGCAUUGCCCGCCGAGCACUGCAUAAACAUCUAUCAGAGGCGCUGCGAAGCCUUUGGGUGGAACACUUAUGUGGUGGACGGCCGGGACGUGGAGGCACUGUGCCAGGUAUUCUGGCAGGCUUCUCAGGUGAAGCACAAGCCCACUGCUGUGGUGGCCAAGACCUUCAAGGGCCGGGGCACCCCAAGUAUUGAGGAUGCAGAAAGUUGGCAUGCAAAGCCAAUGCCGAGAGAAAGAGCAGAUGCCAUUAUCAAAUUAAUUGAGAGCCAGAUACAGACCAGCAGGAAUCUUGACCCACAGCCCCCCAUUGAGGACUCACCUGAAGUCAACAUCACAGAUGUAAGGAUGACCUCUCCACCUGAUUACAGAGUUGGUGACAAGAUAGCUACUCGGAAAGCAUGCGGUCUGGCUCUGGCUAAGCUGGGCUACGCGAACAACAGAGUCGUUGUGCUGGAUGGUGACACCAGGUACUCUACUUUCUCUGAGAUAUUCAACAAGGAGUACCCUGAGCGCUUCAUCGAGUGCUUUAUGGCUGAACAAAACAUGGUGAGCGUGGCUCUGGGCUGUGCCUCCCGUGGACGGACCAUUGCUUUUGCUAGCACCUUUGCUGCCUUUCUGACUCGAGCAUUUGAUCACAUCCGGAUAGGAGGCCUCGCUGAGAGCAACAUCAACAUUAUUGGUUCCCACUGUGGGGUAUCUGUUGGUGACGAUGGUGCUUCCCAGAUGGCCCUGGAGGAUAUAGCCAUGUUCCGAACCAUUCCCAAGUGCACGAUCUUCUACCCAACUGAUGCCGUCUCCACGGAGCAUGCUGUUGCUCUGGCAGCCAAUGCCAAGGGGAUGUGCUUCAUUCGGACCACCCGACCAGAAACUAUGGUUAUUUACACCCCACAAGAACGCUUUGAGAUCGGACAGGCCAAGGUCCUCCGCCACUGUGUCAGUGACAAGGUCACAGUUAUUGGAGCUGGAAUUACUGUGUAUGAAGCCUUAGCAGCUGCUGAUGAGCUUUCGAAACAAGAUAUUUUUAUCCGUGUCAUCGACCUGUUUACCAUUAAACCUCUGGAUGUCGCCACCAUCGUCUCCAGUGCAAAAGCCACAGAGGGCCGGAUCAUUACAGUGGAGGAUCACUACCCGCAAGGUGGCAUCGGGGAAGCUGUCUGCGCAGCCGUCUCCAUGGAUCCUGACAUUCAGGUUCAUUCGCUGGCAGUGUCGGGAGUGCCCCAGAGUGGGAAGUCCGAGGAAUUGCUGGAUAUGUAUGGAAUUAGUGCCAGACAUAUCAUAGUGGCCGUGAAAUGCAUGUUGCUGAACUAAAAUAGCUGUUAGCUUUGGUCUUUUGGCCUCUUUACCCUGUGUUUAUGUUUGUUCCAAAACCAUCAUUUAAAUCUCUACUGUCACAUUUUGUUUCUUAAAAGCAAAGCCAGCUAACACCUUCAUUCAUCCCUAGUUCGGAAAUUCAAGCUAACUACUUACCCUUUAAACUGUCACUGCAUAUGCAAGUACCGCUCUAAUUUUUGGAUCAUUAAAGGGAGUUACACAACUUUUAAGUGAAAAAAAUAGGUAACAAAACAACCACCUGAUAGUAAGUUUUCUGAUAAGACUAUAGAUAAGUGGUAGAGGUAAUCAAUUCUUCCGAAGUGUUUCCUUCGUGAAUAACUGGUAGAGGUAAUAGUUUUUUCAAUGUAUUUCCUUCAUGAGUAAAGAAAAUGUGGAUUGAAGUAUAGAUUCCAGUAGCCUAGUUUCCACAGCACGAUAACACCAUGACGCCUACUGCUGUUCCCACCUUGGGAUUCUGUGUGCUGCCAUCCCACCUGCAGCUGCCCUGGAAUUCCCUUCGCUGUUUGCCUUCAUCUCCCUCCACGUUUGAGAGGCUGUCAGGCAGCAGCGAAAGCUUGUUAGGAUGUCCUGUGCUGCUUGUGAUGAGAGCCUCCACACUGUACUGUUCAAGUCAAUGUUAAUAAAGCAUUUCAAAACCA